UAAGGUAAUGAGCCUUGUCACCCAAAUGCUUUAAACAGAAGCCAUCAUCUGUCACAUGCCAGAGGGUGCCCCUCAAGAGUGGGAGAGCAGGGGCUGAACUGCUGAGUUCCCGCUGCGUCCUGUUGCUAUGCUGCCUGCACCCUUGGUGGGGAGAAGAGAAGAGGUGGACUGCUGCGGAGGACCUGGCAAACAAGGACCCAGAUGCCUAUGGCGUCCCCUCAAACCCUGGUCCUCUAUCUGCUGGUCCUGGCAGUCACUGAAGCCUGGGGCCAGGAGGCAGUCAUCCCAGGCUGCCACUUGCACCCCUUCAAUGUGACAGUGCGAAGUGACCGCCAAGGCACCUGCCAGGGCUCCCACGUGGCACAGGCCUGUGUGGGCCACUGUGAGUCCAGCGCCUUCCCUUCUCGGUACUCUGUGCUGGUGGCCAGUGGUUACCGACACAACAUCACCUCCGUCUCUCAGUGCUGCACCAUCAGUGGCCUGAAGAAGGUCAAAGUACAGCUGCAGUGUGUGGGGAGCCGGAGGGAGGAGCUCGAGAUCUUCACGGCCAGGGCCUGCCAGUGUGACAUGUGUCGCCUCUCUCGCUACUAGCCCAUCCUCUCCCCUCCUUCCUCCCCUGGGUCACAGGGCUUGACGUUCUGGUGGGGGAAACCUGUGUUCAAGAUUCAAAAACUGGAAGGAGCUCCAGCCCUGAUGGUUACUUGCUAUGGAAUUUUUUUAAAUAAGGGGAGGGUUGUUCCAGCUUUGAUCCUUUGUAAGAUUUUGUGACUGUCACCUGAGAAGAGGGGAGUUUCUGCUUCUUCCCUGCCUCUGCCUGGCCCUUCUAAACCAAUCUUUCAUCAUUUUACUUCCCUCUUUGCCCUUACCCCUAAAUAAAGCAAGCAGUUCUUGAA